GGCGAGCGCCGAUCCCGGGGCGCCUGCGCGGGUGGCUUUGCGGGCGCUCGCGGUAAGUUUGCGCCAAGUGCGCGGCAGCCGGGACGCAGACGGCGGCGGCGGCGAGAGGCGGAGCCCGGGGACCACCCCCCAUCACCCUCCCCCCAGUCACCUCACGUACCACAACCUCACGUAACCUCUCACCCCCCCUCCGAUACCCCCAGCCCCGGGAUGGCAGCGCCCGCCAGCCUUCCCGGCCGGACCGGCUGUCGCCAGUGCCGGCUUUAGCCUGUGGGACUAGGCCCCGCCGAGGCCUGACCCCCGGAGCCGGGACCCACUGUGCAGCCAGCAGCCGGGCCGGGACUGAGGGGCCGCUCCCCCCUCGCGGCCCGUCGGGAGGACGCUGUCGUCCCGGGGACUGGGGGCCGGGGGGUGGGGGGGAGCCAGGGCGAGGAAGUCGGGACCCGUAUUGGGAAAAAAGCGGGGCCGGGGUCAGGAGCGCCCCCUCCCCUCACCUCCCCCCUCCCCCCGGGGUUGGGGGGGCCGGAGCAGAGAGCACCCAGCCCGGGAGGUGGAUGAAUGUGGGAGAAAAUGGAGACCAAGACGAUCGUGUACGACUUGGACACAUCAGGGGGGCUGAUGGAGCAAAUCCAAGCUCUGCUGGCUCCCCCCAAGACGGACGAGGCAGAAAAGCGCAGUCGGAAGCCUGAGAAGGAGCCCCGGAGAAGCGGCAGGGCCACCAACCACGACAGCUGCGAUAGCUGCAAGGAAGGUGGAGAUCUCCUGUGCUGCGACCACUGCCCGGCUGCCUUCCACCUCCAGUGCUGUAACCCUCCACUGAGUGAAGAAAUGUUGCCUCCUGGAGAGUGGAUGUGUCACCGGUGCACUGUUCGCCGAAAGAAACGAGAGCAGAAAAAGGAGCUGGGUCAUGUCAAUGGACUGGUGGACAAAUCUGGCAAACGGACUACAUCCCCCAGCAGUGACACUGACUUGUUGGACAGAUCGGCCAGCAAAACUGAACUAAAGGCCAUUGCCCAUGCCCGGAUCCUGGAAAGGAGAGCCAGCAGGCCUGGCACACCCACAUCCAGCGCCAGCACAGAGACUCCCACCUCUGAGCAGAAUGAUGUCGACGAAGACAUCAUUGACGUGGAUGAGGAACCAGUAGCAGCGGAGCCAGACUAUGUGCAGCCCCAGCUGAGGCGGCCCUUUGAGCUGCUGAUUGCUGCCGCCAUGGAGCGGAACCCCACCCAAUUUCAGUUGCCCAAUGAACUGACUUGUACCACUGCACUACCAGGUUCUAGCAAGAGGAGAAGAAAGGAGGAAACCACAGGGAAAAAUGUUAAGAAGACACAGCAUGAAUUAGAUCACAAUGGUCUCGUUCCCUUACCCGUCAAAGUCUGCUUCACGUGUAACAGGAGUUGCCGUGUGGCUCCUCUCAUCCAGUGUGACUAUUGCCCUCUCCUGUUUCACAUGGAUUGCCUCGAGCCGCCGCUCACUGCCAUGCCCCUGGGCAGAUGGAUGUGUCCGAAUCACAUCGAACAUGUGGUGCUGAACCAGAAGAAUAUGACACUGAGCAAUCGGUGCCAGGUGUUUGAUCGUUUCCAGGACACCGUUUCGCAGCAUGUCGUCAAAGUGGACUUCCUGAACCGAAUCCACAAGAAGCACCCCCCUAACCGGCGUGUGCUCCAGUCGGUCAAAAGAAGAAGCUUGAAGGUUCCUGAUGCUAUAAAAUCUCAGUACCAGUUUCCACCCCCUCUCAUUGCACCCGCGGCCAUUCGGGACGGGGAGCUGAUCUGCAAUGGGAUCCCUGAGGAAUCACAGAUGCACCUUUUGAACUCUGAGCACUUAGCCACCCAAGCAGAGCAGCAAGAGUGGCUCUGUAGUGUUGUUGCGCUCCAGUGCAGCAUAUUGAAACAUUUAUCUGCUAAGCAGAUGCCUUCGCAUUGGGACUCUGAACAGACAGAGAAGGCUGAUAUUAAGCCUGUUAUUGUGACUGACAGCUCAGUCACCACCUCCCUGCAAACAGCUGACAAGACACCUACACCUUCCCACUACCCCUUGUCCUGCCCCUCAGGGAUUAGCACCCAGAAUUCCCUGAGCUGCUCUCCACCCCACCAGUCCCCAGCCCUAGAGGACAUCGGCUGCAGUUCUUGUGCGGAAAAAUCCAAGAAAACCCCUUGUGGGACUGCCAAUGGGCCAGUGAACACAGAGGUGAAAGCUAAUGGCCCACACCUCUACAGCAGCCCUACUGAUUCCACGGACCCCCGGCGACUUCCAGGCGCUAACACCCCACUACCAGGCCUCUCACACCGGCAAGGCUGGCCCCGGCCCCUCACGCCACCAGCGGCUGGGGGCCUUCAGAACCACACCGUCGGCAUCAUUGUGAAGACAGAGAAUGCCACUGGCCCCAGCUCUUGCCCCCAGAGGAGUUUGGUUCCUGUCCCAAGCCUGCCCCCUUCCAUUCCCAGCUCUUGUGCCAGCAUCGAGAACACCAGCACUUUGCAAAGAAAGACUGUCCAAUCACAGAUAGGACCUCCGUUGACAGAUUCAAGGCCACUGGGCUCACCCCCAAACGCCACCCGGGUGCUCACUCCCCCGCAAGCAGCAGGAGAUGGUAUCUUGGCCACAACAGCCAACCAACGAUUCAGCUCACCAGCGCCAUCGUCAGAUGGCAAGGUCAGCCCCGGCACGUUAUCCAUAGGAAGCGCUUUAACCGUACCCUCUUUCCCAGCCAACUCUACUGCCAUGGUGGACCUCACCAACUCACUUCGAGCAUUUAUGGAUGUCAAUGGAGAAAUCGAGAUAAAUAUGCUGGACGAGAAGCUGAUCAAGUUUCUGGCCUUGCAGAGAAUACAUCAGCUUUUCCCCUCCCGGGUCCAACCUUCACCGGGCAGUGUCGGGACACAUCAGCUGGCUUCUGGAGGGCACCACAUAGAAGGUGCGCAUGUACACACCUGUCACCACAUCAUCAGAUCUCCCCUCUACGUGUGCGAAUGGUCACCUUGCCUCCAUGGAGAAUCUGAGCUUCCAGUAUCUCAAACCUCCUUGUGUGCUUUUCAUGGGCUUAAUAAAGCACCAUGGUUUUUUUCUGAAGAGAGCAGGAACAAGAUGGCAACCACAGCUUUCUGAUCAGACUUGGGGAAGUCUGCUGUAACUUUCUUUCAUAUAUAAGUCCACUUCGAGACACAGCAAAGCAGCUACCAGUACCUUUGGGUAUAUGUAGUGUACUUUCUGCUUACUUGCUUUCAAAUAUUUGAAUUAGAAGGGCUUCCCGACUGAGUGCAGUGGCUCACACCUGUAAUCCCAGCACUUUGGGAGGCUGAGGCGGGAGGAUCACUUGAGCCCAGGAGUUGGAGACCAGCCUGGGCAACACAGUGAGACCCUAUCUCUACAAAUAAUUUUAAACUUACCCAGGCAUGGUGGCAUACACCUGUAAUCCCAGCUGCUUGGAAGGCUAAGAUGGGAGGAUCGCUUGAGUCUGGGAGGUCAAGGCUGCAGUGAGCUAUGAUUGUGCCACUGCACUCCAGCCUGGGUGACAGAGUGAGACCCUGUCUCCAAAUAAAUAAGUAAAUAAAUAAAUAAAAUUUUAAAAAGAAUGGCUUCCCAAGAGGGAACUUUUCAAGUUCAAGUUGAGAAAUAGAAUAACACUAGGCCAACCUUCUGGAAAUUUUCCCCAAGUGGUUAACUCUGUUUCAGAUAUGUCUGAGCAUUGGCCAUUAAGAGCCUUGCUGCUUCAAAGUGUGGUUCGCAGACCAGCAGCAUCAGCAGCCCCUGAGAGCUUGUUAGAAAUGCAGAGCUCAAUGCAUUGGUUUUUUGCCUAUUUUUAAAGAAAACAGCAAAAGAAAUGCAGAGCUAAGGCCCCUCCUCAGACCUAUUGAAUCAGAAUCUGCAUUUCAACAAGAUCUGUAGGCGAUUCUUAUGCACAUUAAAGUUUGAGAAACACUGGUCCAUGCCGUCUGUUUUUCCAUAUUCUCCCUAUAGUACCAGCUGGAAUAUCCCGGAUUAGCCAGCCAGGAGCCCAGGAACUUACACAGUACUGUCAUCUCUGACUUCUCUGACCAUCUUCAAAGAUGGUCCUCUGUACCCUGUGUUGGAAAUGCUGUGGGUGGGGAGAGAAAGCCUUACCCUGCCGCAGCUCAGUGUUGGAUGUGAGUUUGGAAAGAUGAGUCAUCCAGCGGGAUUUUCUCCAGGCCAUGAGCCAAAGGUCCAGAUUUUGUUGGUUUAUGUUUGGAUCACAGGAUCUGAGUUUCUGAAUGAUCCUAUUCCUAUGUUUGUCUUGUAGUGCAAAGAAAGGAGGUACAGGCCCGAGCUGUGUUCUACCCCCUCUUAGGGUUGGGAGGAGCUGUGAACAUGUGCUAUCGAACCCUCUACAUCGGGACAGGUGAGCCAGCCAGGAAGCUGGGAGAGACACUGAAUCUGUUCAGCCCUAAAGACUGACACCCUUACCCACAGAAGUUAGAAAGGGGUGAGGGAAGCCCUUUCCAGAGUUGACUGCUUUAAAUCAGUGGAUAGCUAGACAAGAGAAACUAAGAAUAGAGACAAUCAGCCAGUCACGGUGGCUCACGCCUAUAAUCCCAACACUUUGGGAGGACAAGGCAGGAGGAACACUUGAGCCCAGGACUUCGAGACCAGCCUGGGCAACAUGGUGAAACCCUAUCUCUACCAAAAACAAAUAUAAAAAAUUAGCUGGGCUAACAUGCCUAUAGUCCCAGCUACUUGGGAGGCUGAGGUGGGAAGAUCACCUGAGGCUGGGAGGUCCAGGCAGUGAUCCUUUUUGUGCCUCUGCACUCCAGCCCAGGCAACAGAGUGAGACCCUGUCUCAAAAAUAAAAGAGACAAUCAGUUCCUUGUCUUCCCUUGUUCAGGCCCUUUUGCUUUGUCUUUGCCCAGUGUUGCAACAGCAGAGAUGAAAGUCAGCUCUGACUACUGCCCAGGGAGGCACUUUAAACACUGCAGGGAAGAACCUAAGGAGAAGGCAGAUGCUUUGUCCCUGGUGGUCUUUGAAAGAGUGAUAGACUCACACAUACCCAAUCUUCAGUUAGCCCUGUAUCUGUUUUUUGUUUUGUUUUGUUUUCCCUAAAAGUCCUAGAGACCGAUAGCUCUGUAUCUGGUACAGAAGGACAGACAGAUUAGCCCUUACCCUAGAAACUUCCCUUUCUUUAAGGUGAUAAGAUUUUCUAGGCUCUGCACCCCGAUGUUGUAUUUUCAUAGAAAUAUCCCAUCCUCUUCAGUAGCUCACUCUUCCCUUCUGGGUAGCAGCCACAUGUUCUAAAGCAGAUCAGCUGGCAGGGACAGCUGUUCUUUAUCAGGAGCUUGGAAAAGACAACAGUUUUUGUUCAAAAAUAAAAGGGGAGGGCCCUGAGCUACUCACCCUUGAAGUCUCUGCUAGUGCCAACCCAGAAGCUAACUCUCUCCCUGUCUUACCUCCCCGACACAUGCACCUUACAAUCUGUUCUCUGCCUUCCUUUUCCUCUACUCCUGCCACCUUGCAGGAGCUGACAUGGAUGUGUGCCUUACAAACUAUGGUCACUGUAACUACGUGUCCGGGAAACAUGCCUGCAUAUUCUACGAUGAGGUGAGGGCCGGAGAUGCGGUGGGAGGGAGCUUUCCCAACCUGAGGCCUCUCCCAGGCAGUAGGUUUUUGUUCAGUGCCCUGAGGGGAGGGAAGAGGGAUUGGGGGUCCUCUCUUUUUCUUCCCUCCCUGUCAUUCCUGGAGGAGGAGAGUCUUGAUGUGAAAUAGCAUCCUACCUGGGAAGCUACCUGCUUCCCAGGAGCAGGGCUACCAUUUUUCCUGAGGUUAGUCACAGGCACAACAGAGGGAGCCUACCCUAAAGCAAGGGAGGGGACCAGCAUAGAAGGAAGCCAAGCCUUGUGGGUGUGUCCCUGUGAAUUUCAUUAUCAUCACGGGCCAGUGAGUAUCAUACCAAGAGGAGCGGUGCUGAGAGGGCAGAGUGAAGGAGUGGGAGAGUAGGGAGUGUGGGACACCAGAAGGAAAGCUUCCCUGAGGAGGUGUCUCCAGCCCCCUUCUGAAAGGACAGGGGCCAUGACUGGGGAGGCAAGUAAGGACUCUCUAGGUAGAGUAGCACGGCCUUCUCCAUAUGUCCUCUCUCCCCUUAGCCCCAGGCCCCACACAGCAGACCACACAUCUUAUCUCCCCUCCUCCUCCUCAGAAUACCAAACAUUAUGAGCUGUUAAACUACAGUGAGCAUGGGACAACGGUGGACAAUGUGCUGUAUUCAUGUGACUUCUCGGAGAAGACCCCGCCAACCCCCCCAAGCAGUAUUGUUGCCAAAGUGCAGAGUGUCAUCAGUAAGUUGGAGCAGAGAUCUGUGGCCACAAAGCUGAGGCCCCAGUCAGGGUGGUUCUGACUUGCUGCCCAUGGUCUGUCUCUUGCCUUCCCAGUCCUAUUGGCCAAGCUCUACUUCCUCGUGGGCCCAGGGCAGGCCACAGAGAAGCAAGUGCUGAGUACCCCCAUGUGUGUACACACCUGUGGGGACUUCAGACUCCACCAACCCUUUCUGAGCAUCCUUCCUCCCUAGUCAUGCAGCAGUUGGAAUGGGGAGAUGCAGGAGCCCAACCUUGGCAAACAGCCCACAUGGGUUGGCUGCUCACUGUUCCUCUUCUGUGACCAUCCCCCUUUUUCCCAGGGCGCCGCCGGCACCAGAAACAGGACGAAGAGCCAAGUGAGGAGGCAGCCAUGAUGAGUUCCCAGGCCCAGGGGCCGCAGCGGAGACCCUGCAAUUGCAAAGCCAGCAGCUCGAGCUUGAUUGGGGGCAGUGGGGCCGGCUGGGAGGGCACAGCCUUACUGCACCAUGGCAGCUACAUCAAGCUGGGCUGCCUGCAGUUUGUCUUCAGCAUCACUGAGUUUGCGACCAAACAGCCCAAAGGCGAUGCCAGCCUGCUGCAGGAUGGGGUCUUGGCCGAGAAGCUCUCUCUCAAGCCCCACCAGGGCCCUGUGCUGCGCUCCAACUCUGUUCCUUAGGACUGGCGGCUACCCCGCCACUGGCCUGUACACCCACCCAAGACUCCUGCAAUGCAAAAAUGUACACAAACCAAGCCCGGGUGUUUUCUAUACUCUACCAGAAACCCUUCAACUACAAUCUUUGCAUGAAAUGAAGAAAACCUUUUGACUGUUUUUUAAAAAUCCUUUUUCUUUUCUCAAGUUCUAGGGGGCAUUUGCACAUAUAUUUGUACUCAACAUUUCAUGGGAAAGCGGCAGACCUGAGCUGAGGAACAGCGUGGGCAGGGAGGGAAAGACCCAGGGUCUGGACACUUCCUCCAACACAAAACCCUUCCCCACCCACCUCCUGCUCCCUCCCCCUCGCCCACCAUUGUAAAAUAAUCAGAAACUUGUUCUAUUUUGUGGCAGUGACAAUAGUUUUAUAUUAAAAGAAAAAAUACAGUUUUCAUACAGCAAAAUCUAUACAAUAUCAUUGUUUUAUUUAAUAUAAAGAUCGCUACCCACCUUCCUUCCAUGGUUCCCACCCUCCACGUUAUUUUCCCUUUCUGCAGCGGUUGCACUACAGGUAGCUACUGUGUAUUAUGGACAAAUGAGAAAUGAAUUCUUUUUCUGGCUGUCCAUCUAUUUUAUUUCAAAUAAGGAAAAGUGUAUUUGGAUUUUGUGUAAAUACAUCUAGUGAUGACAUUUUUUCAAUGUUUUUAAAAACCGUGUACAGUACUACAUGUGGUAGAGCGUUUUCUCAAAUUGUCUAUUGUAGCAAAAAUGUUUUUGUCGUAAACCUGUUUUGUCUCCUUUUUUUGUUCUCUUGCCACUUCUCUCCUCUUCCUCCUGCCCCUGGUUCCCUCCUCUCCUCCCACCCCCACAACCAGUACCAAUGUACAUAGUAAUUGUAAUGUUUUAGACUUUACAGAAACUUUCCUGUAUUCUGUAUAUAAAAAACAAAAAUACUUCAAA